ACCGGAAGCACCGCCAUUGGCCGGUGCGUGCAGGUGGCAGCCAAGAGCCUCCUGGCACAGCGGCACCAGGCAGGUGACGCCUAUUGGACCCCAGAGGUCAUCCCAGCUCCAGACGUGGACACAUUUUCUUCCAAUGAUGUCUACGGAUGAGGAAACUGAGGCCUGGAGAGGUUAAAGAGACCCGUUCAGAGUCCUACAGUGGCAGGACUUGAGUGCUUGAUUUGCCUGAAGAAUGUUAUGUGUCUGUUCAGAAGAGAGAUUAGGACCUGCGAAGCUCAUGCCUAGAGGGGAGAGUAUUCCUGCAGAAUUCAGCGUAGGAAAGGAGGCCUCAGGCACCAGAAGUGUUUGAGAGCAGGAGAGUUCUCAGAAGAGAUUGCCUGGGAAAUGAGAGCAUCGCUGGGGUGAAGUCCCAGCAGCUGCGAGUGUUGAGGCUGCUGUGAGGUGGCCCAUGCUUAGGCUCUGUGUUCCUGGCCAGAGUGAGUCCCCAGCACCGCAACAUCUGCAGGAGAUGAUGCUGGUGGAAGAGGUUUCCCAAGCCUUUGAAGGGAAAGACUGGUCUUCUGAGGACCUCUGCCCUCUACACAGCGGCCUCUUCAGGUGCAGGGAGGAAAUGGAAGCACGUUCUAUGCUGGUUCCACCCCAGGCAUCUGUGUGCUUCGAGGAUGUGGCUAUGGCAUUCACACAGGAGGAGUGGGAACAGCUGGACCUGGCCCAGAGGACACUGUACCGAGAGGUGACACUGGAGACCUGGGAGCAUAUUGUCUCCCUGGGGCUUUUCCUUUCCAAAUCUGAUGUGAUCUCUCAGCUGGAGCAAGAAGAGGACCUGUGCAGGGCAGAGCAGGAGGCCCCCCGAGACGGAGUUUCGCUCUUGUUGCCCAGACUGGAGUGCAAUGGCACAAUCUCGGCUCACCACAACCUCCACCUCCCAGGUUCAAGUGAUUCUCCUGCCUCAGCCUCCCAAGUAGCUGGGAUUACAGGCAUGUCCACCAUGCCCGGCUAAUUUUUUGUAUUUUUAGUGGAGACAGAGUUUCACCGUGUUAGCCAGGAUGGUCUUGAUCUCCUGACCUCAUGAUCCGCCCGCCUCAGCCUCCCAAAGUGCUGAGAUUACAGGUGUGAGCCAUCACGCCUGGCCCUAAUUUUGUAUUUUUAUUAGAGGUGGGGUUUCUCCAUGUUGGUCAGGCUGGUCUCGAACUCCCGACCUCAGGUGAUCCACCUGCCUCAGCCUCCCAAAGUGCCGGGAUUACAGGUAUGAGCCACUGCACCUGGCCAUUAAUUUUUGUAUUUUUAAUGGAGAUAGGGUUUCAUCAUGUUGCCCAGGCUAAUAGACUUUAUUUUUUAGAGCAGUUUUAGGUUUAUAGGUAAGUUGACGAGAAAGUGCAGAGUUCCCACCCAUGUCUGCUGUCCUACAGACACAUGCAGUGUCUCCUGCUGUUAACAACUUGGAUUUGUAUUGUACAUCUGUUACAAUCGGCAAACCUAUCUUGAGGCAUCCUUUUUUUUUUUCCCAGACAGAGUCUCACUCUGUCACCAGGCUGGCGUACAGUGGUGUGAUCUCAGCUCACUGCAACCUCCGCCCCCCAGGUUCAAGUGAUUUUCCUGCCUCAACCUCCCAACUAACUGGGACUACAGGCACGCACCACCACGCCCAGCUAAUUUUUGUAUUUUUAGUAGAGUCAGAGUUUCACCAUGUUGGCCAGGAUGGUCUCGAUCUCCUGACCUCAUGAUGCGCCCCCCUCAGCCUCCCAAAGUGCUGGGAUUACAGGCGUGAGCCACUACCCCUUGCCCUUGAGGCAUCAUUAUCACCCAAAGUCCAUAGUUUAUGAUAGGGUUCAUGCUUUUUUUUUUCUUUUUUUUUUUUUUUUUUUGAGACAGUGAUGCAGUCAUAGCUUAAGCCUUCUGGGCUUAAGUGAUCCUCCCACCUCUCUGCACCCCAGCCUCAGGUGCCACAGCAUGCACCACCAUGCCUGGCUAAUGUAAAAAUUUUUUGUAGAGAUGGAGUGUCACUGUGUUGCCCAGGCUUGUCUUGAACUCCUGGGCUCAAGUGAUCCUCCCACCUCAGCCUCCCAAAGUGCUGGGAUUACAUGUAUGAGCCACUGCACCUGGCCAGGCUUCACUCCUGAUGUUGUAUAUUCUGUGCAUUUGGACAAAUGUACAAUGUCAUGUAUCCACCAUUAUAGUAUCAGACAGAGUAGUUCCACUACCCUAAAUAUUCUCUGUGCUCUACCCAUUCAUCCCUCCCUCAUCCCCAGCCCCUGGUGUUACUGGUGGAGGAUGUGCAGGUUCUUGGCAUUUUGAACAAAGAAUUGGACAAAAUGCAUAAAACAAUGAAAGAAUGAAGCAAAAAAAGCAUAGAUUUAUCAAAAUGAAAGUACACUCCACACAAUGGGAGUGGUCUGGAGCAAGCAGCUCAAGAGCACUGGUUACAGAAUUUUCUGGGGUUUAAAUCCCGAGAGGUUUCCCAUUGGUUACUUGGUUUAUAUCCUCUGUAAAUGAAGUAGUGGCCCAUAACUAGUCUGAUUGGUUGGGGAAGGUGACCAACAGAGGCUGAAGUGAAGUUACAAAGUUACACCUCUAUGCAGAUGAAAACUAGGCCAGUGACCAGUCUCAUUGGUUGCAGGAAGAGGUACUUUCCAUUUUUCAUCUGCGACACAGAAGGCGGGGGUUGCCUCUGAUCCUUUUGUUAUUUGGGGCAUGGAAAGUUUGGGUUUUCCUUUUGAUUCAGUUCCAGGAAGUCAGCAUUAAUCACCCUUAGGUUUCUUGCCUCCAUACCCUGUUCUCAUACCUCAUUUCCCCCCGAAAGACAUGAUCCUCAUAAAUCUUUAUGGGAGGUAAAGGGAUUGAUAGUCUUUCUUCUGUAACUGCUUUAUGCUGACCUGAGGCACAGUCCCUACGUACUGGGGAAUCACAGGACUCUCUCCCCGCCCUGUCUAGUGGAGACAGGAUAGCUUCUUGAUGGCCAGGGGUGGUGUCUCCACCUGGAACUGGCUGGAAACAUUGUCACAUGAUCAUCUGAAGCUUGAUGGUCUCUAGGUGACAGGAAAUGAAUUUGGUUAAGAGUUUAACAAACAUGGUCCAAAAACCAAGGCAAGUAUAGUCAUUACUAAUGGGCUGGCCAGAGGAAGGAGCCAUGAACCCCAACUUAGCAUUUUUGACCAGGAGCCCCAUGACUCAGAUAGCUGUUGUUGUAUUUUAGAGGCCCAGUUGGGUAGUUUUUGGGUGGCAUUUGUUACUAAUCCUCAUUGUUCGGCAUAAAAACAGCAUUCUUCCUCUAGAAAAAGACCUAAGCCCCCCUUUACAGCAGUUAGGAGAUCUCAUCCCCUUCUGUUUUGCCAAGCAACUGCUGCUGAGGCAUCUAUUUGAUUUCGUAUGGUGAUGAUACUUUGGCCAAUGUCUCUAUUUUUUCUUUUUUACUUUGGGCAAUGUCAUUCAAGCUUUCCAUAAAAUCCUUGGAAAAGCAUUGGUAAUAGGAUAGGGAUGUUACAACCCGGCUGACUCCCAUUCCCAGUCCCGCGGUUAUUUGUAGUCCUACCAAAAGGGAUGUGAGUUGGAUGGUUCAUUUGUGUCUGGCAAUUGCAGUUAAAGGUAUAAUGAGGGAUUGGUUCUUGGGAGCUAUAUUAAUUUCACAGGCUAAAUAAACAAGUGUAAAGGUUCUAGUCCAAUUGGCUGGUAAACAUAAGUAAGAACUAGUUCCACACAGGUAAAAGGCUCCUAGUUUUUCAAGACAAGAAUUUUCUAUGGUAAACAUGUGGGUUAGCUUGUUGUUUUCACUUUCCCAAGUGGUUAAGGUCCCUAUGAAGGUGGCCCCAGUUAAAGGCUGGAAAGGACCUUGGGAAAUAUUCUGAGUUGCCCCAGCAGUUCUGUUUUCCCAUUGGAGGUAAUUAGGCUUAGUGUCUACCAACAAGCAUCCAGAGGUGUUUCGUACUGGGGAACCAAAAGAUAACUAGAUGUCUGAGGAUUAGUGCAGUCUUCCCAAGGGAAAAUAUGAUCAUAGCUAGUGGGCUUACCUUGGCAGUACUUAGACUGUGUAUCCUUUGAAGUGUCCUUAUCUAGGGAUGGUUUCCAUGAAAACCAUACAGGUUUUCUAAAUGACACAGUCUGGGUAACUGCCUAGCUUAUGUAAUCAUGUGAGGGGUUAAUAAUCUCUAGGGUGUAGUUACACUGAUGACUUUUCAAGGUUCCCAGGGCCUGACCAAAAUUUUGGCUUCUCUUAAUACAAAGUGGCACCUGGAAUUUUAGCUCUGUGUACAUUGAUAUUGGGCCCCAAAUGGGUUUCUGUGGGAUGCAACCCCAGAAAGGGUACUCUGAUAGUACUGGAGAAGGUUUACUGCUUGUCCUGUCAUCGUAGUUCAUGUUUUUUUCCCCAAGGCCAAAGAUUGGGCUGGGAUUGGGGUGGUAGUGUAUUUGAAUGAUGCUGGAGAUAACCAAAGCCAACAGUCUUUGCCAGAGCUGGGCUGGUGGUAUUUAACUGUCUUUGAGUUAAAUGUAAAGUUUUUAAUAAAUACCCAGAAUCCAUUAACUGCUGGAGGGGUAAAGUGAAGCUCUGUUGUAAAAUAAAGCUGAUUCCCAUUAUGCGUGGUCCUGUAUACACAGGCUGUGGGUGACCAUUAUGGAACCAAAAAAUACUUAUUUGUUAUUUUGUGCUAUAGAAUAGGAACUUCAGGGGUGGAUACCUAUGCUGUCAGGAAUGCUUGUUAUAAGAAUUAAUUAAAACACUUUGCUUAAUUAUUA